GCACUCGCAGGCGACCUGCUCCAGUCUCCAAAGCCGAUGGCAUCUCCGGGCUCUGGCUUUUGGUCUUUCGGGUCGGAAGAUGGCUCUGGGGAUUCCGAGAAUCCCGGCACAGCGCGAGCCUGGUGCCAAGUGGCUCAGAAGUUCACGGGCGGCAUCGGAAACAAACUGUGCGCCCUGCUCUACGGAGACGCCGAGAAGCCGGCGGAGAGCGGCGGGAGCCAACCCCCGCGGGCCGCCGCCCGGAAGGCCGCCUGCGCCUGCGACCAGAAGCCCUGCAGCUGCUCCAAAGUGGAUGUCAACUACGCGUUUCUCCAUGCAACAGACCUGCUGCCGGCGUGUGAUGGAGAAAGGCCCACUUUGGCGUUUCUGCAAGAUGUUAUGAACAUUUUACUUCAGUAUGUGGUGAAAAGUUUCGAUAGAUCAACCAAAGUGAUUGAUUUCCAUUAUCCUAAUGAGCUUCUCCAAGAAUAUAAUUGGGAAUUGGCAGACCAACCACAAAAUUUGGAGGAAAUUUUGAUGCAUUGCCAAACAACUCUAAAAUAUGCAAUUAAAACAGGGCAUCCUAGAUACUUCAAUCAACUUUCUACUGGUUUGGAUAUGGUUGGAUUAGCAGCAGACUGGCUGACAUCAACAGCAAAUACUAACAUGUUCACCUAUGAAAUUGCUCCAGUAUUUGUGCUUUUGGAAUAUGUCACACUAAAGAAAAUGAGAGAAAUCAUUGGCUGGCCAGGGGGCUCUGGCGAUGGGAUAUUUUCUCCCGGUGGCGCCAUAUCUAACAUGUAUGCCAUGAUGAUCGCACGCUUUAAGAUGUUCCCAGAAGUCAAGGAGAAAGGAAUGGCUGCUCUUCCCAGGCUCAUUGCCUUCACGUCUGAACAUAGUCAUUUUUCUCUCAAGAAGGGAGCUGCAGCCUUAGGGAUUGGAACAGACAGCGUGAUUCUGAUUAAAUGUGAUGAGAGAGGGAAAAUGAUUCCAUCUGAUCUUGAAAGAAGGAUUCUUGAAGCCAAACAGAAAGGGUUUGUUCCUUUCCUCGUGAGUGCCACAGCUGGAACCACCGUGUACGGAGCAUUUGACCCCCUCUUAGCUGUCGCUGACAUUUGCAAAAAGUAUAAGAUCUGGAUGCAUGUGGAUGCAGCUUGGGGUGGGGGAUUACUGAUGUCCCGAAAACACAAGUGGAAACUGAGUGGCGUGGAGAGGGCCAACUCUGUGACGUGGAAUCCACACAAGAUGAUGGGAGUCCCUUUGCAGUGCUCUGCUCUCCUGGUUAGAGAAGAGGGAUUGAUGCAGAAUUGCAACCAAAUGCAUGCCUCCUACCUCUUUCAGCAAGAUAAACAUUAUGACCUGUCCUAUGACACUGGAGACAAGGCCUUACAGUGCGGACGCCACGUUGAUGUUUUUAAACUAUGGCUGAUGUGGAGGGCAAAGGGGACUACCGGGUUUGAAGCGCAUGUUGAUAAAUGUUUGGAGUUGGCAGAGUAUUUAUACAACAUCAUAAAAAACCGAGAAGGAUAUGAGAUGGUGUUUGAUGGGAAGCCUCAGCACACAAAUGUCUGCUUCUGGUACAUUCCUCCAAGCUUGCGUACUCUGGAAGACAAUGAAGAGAGAAUGAGUCGCCUCUCGAAGGUGGCUCCAGUGAUUAAAGCCAGAAUGAUGGAGUAUGGAACCACAAUGGUCAGCUACCAACCCUUGGGAGACAAGGUCAAUUUCUUCCGCAUGGUCAUCUCAAACCCAGCGGCAACUCACCAAGACAUUGACUUCCUGAUUGAAGAAAUAGAACGCCUUGGACAAGAUUUAUAAUAACCUUGCUCACCAAGCUGUUCCACUUCUCUAGGUAGACAAUUAAGUUGUCACAAACUGUGUGAAUGUAUUUGUAGUUUGUUCCAAAGUAAAUCUAUUUCUAUAUUGUGGUGUCAAAGUAGAGUUUAAAAAUUAAACAAAAAAGACAUUGCUCCUUUUAAAAGUCCUUUCUUAAGUUUAGAAUACCUCUCUAAGAAUUCGUGACAAAAGGCUAUGUUCUAAUCAAUAAGGAAAAGCUUAAAAUUGUUAUAAAUACUUCCCUUACUUUUAAUAUAGUGUGCAAAGCAAACUUUAUUUUCACUUCAGACUAGUAGGACUGAAUAGUGCCAAAUUGCCCCUGAAUCAUAAAAGGUUCUUUGGGGUGCAGUAAAAAGGACAAAGUAAAUAUAAAAUAUAUGUUGACAAUAAAAACUCUUGCCUUUUUCAUAGUAUUAGAAAAAAAUUUCUAAUUUACCUAUAGCAACAUUUCAAAUGUAUUUAAAUACAUAUAAUUUUACAAAAGGAAAAUAUAUAUAUUAAAAAAGAUAUCCUAUUUUGUAACAUAUAGAUUUUUAUUUUAUAUAGGUUAUACAAACUGCGGGGGCAGAUAUAAAAUCUAAGCCAGAUUUUUUUUUCCUUUCUCUUAAUGGAGGCACAAUAAAACACUUAGCAAAGUUAUUUUGAAACAUUGACCCACGAAAUUCUUAAAAGGUAUUAUUGCUUCUUUCUAUACAUGUUAUGGCUUAUCACAUCUCUAAAGUUAGUAUUUCAAGACAAACACAAAAGAAUACUGCGAGUUCUUUAAAAUAAUUGAUCCCAUUGGCAGUAAGAUUCUCUUCCCCUUUAAGUUUUCCACCCAUUUUACUCUUAGCGGACUCACUCUGCAAGCGUGACAAACCAGGCUUCAUCUCAGAUUAAAUUAGGGUAAUUGUCUCUAUUCUGCUUUCCAGUUCGGCCUGUUUUGAACAGAAGGUUGAUGCUAGUUCUUGAGGCAUCUUCCAAAUAGUAUUCUUUUAUUAGGUCAUUUGAAUUAAUUAGAGAAAGUAAAAAUAAAACCUUAUCAGCCUGAGCAAAGAGGAAUGAAGCACACUCCCAGAAUGUGGUGAGCCCAGAAAAUUAAAGUUGGCCUUGGGAGAAGAGAUCUCUGUGGGACAAUAAUGACAUCAUCCUGGCGCCAUAUUGCCACUGUCCAGGAAAGAGAAAUUUACCUCCAGGCCAGUUGCGCAUUUCCAUCCCCUCCCCAUUCCUCCCCACAAAGUCUCUCCCACUAGACUCCCUACCACUGGGACCCAAAAUAGUUACUUUAUAUUCCAUGGGUGGUUGUUUUUCUUCCAUGAAAUGAGCCUCUCACCCUAGAUUUUGAGGCAUUAUCUUAAGAUUUUCCUUUAUCCAUCUCCCAUCGAGAUCCAAAGUGACCAGAAUAUGCAGAAAUAAUAAGAUCCUUAGAAUUCAAAAUAGUAUUUUUAAAACAUCCUUCUUUCCCUGUGAACCUGAUAGAAAAACAUGAGCUAACAAAAGCUUCCAUAGAUAUUUAUGGGGUCACACAUCGUCAGAUUCCAAGUGCUGAUUGGAGAACAAUAGAUUGAUAUGCAGACUGCAAAUGCAAAUUUAGGAACAUUCUCCAUUUCUGAAUGGACCAGGUAGUUCAGUACUCAGACUGCAGGUAUACAAGGGAAGAGAGAAGGCCCUGCCCUUCAACGGGUAGAAAUGCCCUACAAUAUAACAUAGAGAAAUGCCCUAUAAUAUAACCACAGGAUCCAGCCAUCUGAAAUUUUCAUAAGCUUCCCCCUACAUUAUUUCUCCUAGGCUAUAUGCAAAAACAGUGAUAACUUGAUAUGAACAUGGCUUUGGGCCCUUUCUGUCUAGAAAAACAAAUGGGUUCACUAUGACAAUCAGAAAUAAACUCUUUCAUCUGUCCCGCAGAAUUUCAUGAAGGAGUAACCUUCCAUUCUAGGCUUUGUCUAAUGGCCAAGCAUUAGACAAAGCAUUAGAAAGCAGUUCCUUUCUCAAAACUGCCUGCUGAGAAUAAGCACAUAGCUGCCCGACUAUCCGGAGCCUCAGGCCCAAAGGUUCCACUUCAGAGACAGAGAUGCUAAUUGAUCCAACCUGCUGUCCUUCGUGGAGAAGACAGUGGGGCCCAGUGCCCUGGUGAACCAACCCUGCUGUACUCCAGGAUGCUUUAUCUUUUGAGUUACAGAUCCUAGAUUAUAAACUGCUGCUUUUUAGGUUAAUGAGAUGGUAAAAUUUUAAAGGACAAUUUGUGCCUAUAUAUGAAAUUCCAGCAAAACAAUUCUAGCAACAACAAUAGCUCUUCUUCCCCGCUCCCCUACCCCUUCCCAGUACUCCUUCAAAUUGGCUGAGAGCCUUGCUCAGGCCUGUGCAGGGAAAUCCUUACCAACUGUAGCCCAAAGAAGGAAGCAAAUAAAAGCCUAGUAGGUCCCAGUAGUUUAAUAAAUCAUCUUGAAAGGAGAUGUGGAAUCAGGUCAGAAGAGAGUAAGGGAGGAAGGGAGGGAGGGAGGGAGGGAGGGAAGGAGGGAGGGAGGAAGGAAAUGAAGGGAGGGAGGGAGGGAGGAAAGAAGGGAGAUUAUUUUUAAUAUUAGCCCAAAUUCCCAGUGCCAUGGUCUUUAUGUGUGCCCAUUCUUUACAAAUCUUAGAAAAGUUUGGUUUUAGCUUUAAUCAGAACUGACAUGGCCAUUUUCAUUUAUACAGCAAUAUUGUGUUUAUCAUUUAAAAUACUUGAACAAACAAGUGUGAUAUGUCUUUAUCUGAGACCUAUACAUGGUAUGGACUUCAUAUACUGCCACAGGAUGUGAGGAAAGAAAAGGAAAUCAAUUCUGACUGUGUUGCCUUUAUUAUCUGGAUAAUACUGUCUUGUCACCUCAGAUUGGGGUUGUGCACUUUAGAUCUGAACUGUACAGUGUUGCAAAUCAACAUGUGUUUCUGUAAAAGCUUGUACAAUAUAUUAUUGAUAUGUCUUUUUCUGUGUGGUAGCUGUAUUGAACUUUGAUAUUAUGAAAACUACAUUUGCAUCUGUUCCUGUUCUCUCUCUCUCUCUCUUUCCUAACUAUAUGCCCUCCACAUCGGCUCUAAUAGAGAACAUGCCCUCAGCUAAGCCCCCUACUGAGAAACUUCCUUUGAGAAUUGUGCGACUUCACAAAAUGCAAGGUGAACACCACUUUGUCUCUGAGAACAGACGUUACCAAUUAUGGAGUGUCACCAGCUGCCAAAAUCGUAGGUGUUGGCUCUGCUGGUCACUGGAGUAGUUGCUACUCUUCAGAAUAUGGACAAAGAAGGCACAGGUGUAAAUAUAGUAGCAGGAUGAGGAACCUCAAACUGGGUAUCAUUUUGCACGUGCUCUUCUGUUCUCAAAUGCUAAAUGCAAACACUGUGUAUUUAUUAGUUAGGUGUGCCAAACUACCGUUCCCAAAUUGGUGUUUCUGAAUGACAUCAACAUUCCCCCAACAUUACUCCAUUACUAAAGACAGAAAAAAAUAAAAACAUAAAAUAUACAAACAUGUGGCAACCUGUUCUUCCUACCAAAUAUAAACUUGUGUAUGAUCCAAGUAUUUUAUCUGUGUUGUCUCUCUAAACCCAAAUAAAUGUGUAAAUGUGGACACA